GCCCCGCCCGUUGCGCCGCCGGCAGGAGGCGCCGCGGCACGCGCGGGUCUGGGCGCCGGCCCCAGCCAACGGCGGGUGGGAGCAGCGCGGGAACGUGGCGGCGCGGCGGGUUGUGCCGGAGGUCACGGCCUCCCCACAUCCUUUGGCUGAAGCCCACAGUCCUCAUCCAUGAAGCCUCACCCACCAUGUUUUAUGGGACGCACUUCAUCAUGUCCCCGCCCACCAAGAGCAAACUGAAGCGGCAGAGCCAGCUGUUGUCCAGCAUGCUGUCCCGGACGCUGAGCUACAAGUACCGGGACCUGGACUCCACCUUCUCCAGCCUGGGCGCCAGCGAUGACCCCGCCGAGCUCUCCACCCAGCUGUCGGCCCCUGGUGUCCUGAAGGUGUUUGGGGACAGUGUCUGCACAGGAACCCACUACAAGAGCGUCCUGGCCACCGGCACCUCCAGCGCCCGUGAGCUGGUGAAGGAGGCGCUGGAGCGGUACGCCCUGGACCCCAGGCAGGCCGGCCAGUACGUGCUGUGUGACGUGGUGGGCCAAGCCGGCGAUGCUGGGCAGCGGUGGCAGGCCCGGUGCUUUCGGGUGUUUGGGGACAGUGAGAAGCCCCUCUUGAUCCAGGAAUUAUGGAAACCCCGAGAAGGUUUAUCCCGGAGGUUUGAGCUGAGGAAGAGGUCGGACGUGGAGGAGCUGGCAGCCAAGGAGGUGGACACCAUCACGGCAGGGAUAAACGCCCAGGCCCGGAGGCUGCAGCGGAGUCGCGCGAAGGGAACCCCGACCCCGGCCCUGGGGGAUGCCCGGAGCUCUCCUCCACCCCGGUUGCGCCGCACAGUCAGUGAGACCAGCCUGAGCCCAGUGAACGCCCUGCCCGCUGCCGCCCAGGGCCCCGAGGAGCCCGGCCCCGACGCCAUGCGGUACUCGCUGUACCAGUCCCCGCAUCUGCUCCUUCUGCAGGGCUACAGCCAGCAGCACGACAGCCUGGUGUAUGUGCUCAACCGGGACCGGCACACGGUGGGCCAGCGGACCCCCUCCAGCAAGCCCAGCAUCAGCCUCUCAGCCCCCGACAUCCUGCCUCUACACUGCACCAUCCGCCGGCAACCGCUCCCGGACAGCGGCCAGGCCGCGGGGAGGCUGGUCCUGGAGCCCAUCCCCGGGGCGCACAUCUCCGUCAACUUCUCCGAGGUGGGGCACAGGACCGUGGUGCUGCACCACGGGGACCUGCUCUCCCUGGGGCUCUACUACCUGCUGCUAUUCAAGGACCCCGCGCAGGCCCAGCCCCUGCCCGCCCGGGCCUUGGCGCGCCUCCGGGCUGUGCCGCAGAGCUGCCGGCUGUGCGGGGCCGCGCUCGGGGCCCGGGGAGCCGCCUCCCCUACUCAGGCCGCCCUGCCCCGGCGCCAGCAGCUGCUCCUGGAGUUUGAGCCCCACCUGGAGGACACGCUGCUGCAGAGGAUCAUGACGUUGAUCGAGCCGGGGGGCGACGACCACAAGCUGACCCCCGCCUUCCUCCUGUGCCUCUGCAUCCAGCACUCGGCCACCCACUUCCAGCCGGGCACAUUCGGGCAGCUCCUGCUCAAGAUAGCCAGGCUGAUCCGCGAGACUGUCUGGGAGAAAACCAAAGAACUAGCAGAGAAGCAGGCGCAACUCCAGGAGCCCAUCUCGCUGGCCAGCUGCGCCAUGGCUGAUCUGGUUCCAGACUUGCAGCCCAUUCUUUUCUGGAUGUCUAACUCCAUCGAGCUCCUGUACUUUAUCCAGCAGAAAUGCCCACUCUACAUGCAGAGCAUGGAGGAGCAGCUGGACAUCACAGGCUCGAAGGAAUCGCUGUUCUCCUGCACGCUGACGGCCAGCGAGGAGGCCAUGGCGGUGCUGGAGGAGGUGGUGCUGUACGCCUUCCAGCAGUGCGUCUACUAUGUCUCCAAGUCCCUGUACAUCUGCCUCCCGGCACUCCUGGAGUGCCCGCCAUUCCAGACGGAGCGCCGUGAGAGCUGGUCCUCGGCCCCCGAACUGCCCGAGGAGCUGCGCCGCGUGGUGUCUGUGUACCAGGCAGCCCUGGACCUCCUGCGGCAGCUGCAGGUGCACCCCGAGGUGGCCUCGCAGAUGCUCGCCUACCUCUUCUUCUUCUCCGGGACACUGCUUCUCAACCAGCUCCUCGACAGGGGCCCCUCCCUGAGCUGCUUCCACUGGCCCAGAGGUGUCCAGGCCUGCGCCCGCCUGCAGCAGCUCCUGGAGUGGAUGCGGAGCGCCGGCUUCGGGGCGGCUGGAGAGCACUUCUUCCAGAAGCUCUCCUGCACCCUCAACCUGCUGGCCACACCCAGGGCCCAGCUCAUCCAGAUGAGCUGGACAGCCCUGCGGGCUGCGUUCCCCGCACUGAGCCCAGCACAGCUGCACCGGCUGCUGACUCACUACCAGCUGGCCUCGGCCAUGGGCCCCAUGAGCACCUGGGAGCCAGGGGCCCAGGACAGCCCCGAGGCCUUCAGGUCAGAGGAUGUUCUGGAGUCCUACGAAAACCCCCCACCCAUCGUCCUGCCCAGCGACGGCUUCCAGGUGGACUUGGAAGCCAACUGCCUGGACGACAGCAUCUACCAGCACCUGCUCUACGUCCGCCACUUUCUGUGGGGUCUGCGGAGCAGAGCCAGCCCCGGCAGCCCUGGCAGGCCUGGCAGUGGGGCCUCCCAGCCAGUGUGCCCCGAGGGUAUGCACCACGUGGUCCUUGACGGGCACCUGGAGGCCCCGAGCUGCCCCCUGGCUCCCAGGGACCCUGGCCCAGCAGCCCGGGAAGUGGCCCCGGAGCGUACUCUUCCCUUGAGGGGGGCUCCCUGGGCACAGGCCCCCCCUGGAAGGCAACCCAGCCGUGGGGGCUCCCAGGCUGGCCCCCCGCACACGGACUCGUCCUGCUUGCUCACGCCUCCCAGCACUCCACUUGGCCCUGAGCCUGGGGACCCCGACUGGCCAGAGUCCGGCGGCCCCUGUGGAAAAGCGCUCCCAGAGAGGCAGAGGAACGGACUCAGCGGCCUCCGGGGUGCAGCUCCGGAAGGAGACUCUGCAGCCCUUGCGGAGGAGUCCCCUCCAGCCCCGUCCAGCCGCAGCUCCAGCACCGAGGACUUCUGCUACGUCUUCACGGUGGAGCUGGAACGAGGCCCCUCCGGGCUGGGGAUGGGCCUGAUCGACGGGAUGCACACGCACCUGGGCGCCCCCGGGCUCUACAUCCAGACCCUGCUCCCGGGCAGCCCCGCAGCGGCCGACGGGCGCCUGUCGCUGGGGGACCGUAUCCUGGAGGUGAAUGGCAGCAGCCUCCUGGGCCUUGGCUACCUGAGAGCUGUGGACCUGAUCCGUCAUGGCGGGAAGAAGAUGCGGUUCCUGGUCGCGAAGUCCGACGUGGAAACAGCCAAGAAGAUCCAUUUCCGCACGCCCCCUCUCUAGGGGGGCUGCGAGGACACCCCCACAGGCCCGGCACCCGGUCCCACCUGGUGACACUGGGCUUCCUCCCGCCUUCGUCCCUGUUUUGUAACUGACCAAGUUGGGUCCCGGGUGGGGAGCCUCACCCUGGGGACAUGCCUGUUGAUAACAUGCAUCUCAGUGUAGGUUCUAUUUAUAUGGCAGAUGACGUGAAAUUGUGAUGUUUGUUACAGAGCUUUUAUGUUUAAAGACUUCAAUGGAGAAGUACGGUUCAAUAAACUAUUUUUCCCGUUCUUAGAGGGUGCCCUGCUGGGGUCUCAACUCGGGCAGCAGGCGUGGGCUGCUCGGAGGGGCCGCAGGGGCUCCCCAUGGCCUCUGCCUGCCACCGGCACGGGAGAAUGCAGUGACAGCUGUCAUCAGGGGAUCAUCUGAACUGACUCUCCCUGCCCCCGUCCCACCCAGACACAGGGCACUGCAGGAAGCAGCUCCAACAGCCCCUCCCAGCUGAAGCAGGGCCAGACCUGGCAGAGGAUGCUGGACUUCUGAUCCCGCUGCUCAGCACAGGCCCCAGAGAAAGGUCUAGACACCCAGGCGUUGGAAAGUGGACCGGCCUGAUGGUCUCUGAGGCGCCGAGCCCACCCUGGGCCCUGCUUCCUCUCCCAGGACUCCUGCUCCCUCCUGAGUUCCUCUCCCCUACUAAAGCCACCAGCGUGGCCCUGAUACCAGGCUGGCGGCCCCAGGCCCUUAAUCCUCACCAGCGUCCCCCUGGCCACCGGCCCUAACCCGGGCAGGAGGCCAGCGUCCCUCUCCACCAGCUGGCUGACCAUGCGCAGGACCAGGGCAGGGCACUUGCUGCCUCGGGGUGACAGCGUGGGUCGCUGGGCAUCCUCAGCAGCUCCACCAACUGGGUGUGGGUGGCUUCCGCGCCCUCCUGGCUGUGGUGGAACUGGUGGCCCAGGGUCAUCUUUGAUAGCAACAGAGAAACCCUGGGGAAGAGGGUCCCGGCAUCAGUUGCAGAUGCACCUCUCACUGGGACAGAGGUCUGUGCGGGGUCCCCAGAUCGGUGUCCUGGGUCUGUCCCAGGCCCUGGGCCUCGUGCAGCUCCACGCUGCCCCCUGGUGUGCGCUACGGCGAGGUGCAGCGCGUCCGCCCCGCGCCCUCUGCCGACCCGCAGUUCUGUGUGCGGCUCCGCAUUGCGCCUGGCUCGAAACGGCGACCACUGCCAGGUUCCCAAAAUACUGGAUAAAAUAUAUAUAUAUAUAUAGUGUUUGUAUAUAUAUUUAAGAUAUGUAAAAUAUAUGAAUAUAUAUAAAUAUAUAAUUAUAUAUGAAUAUAUUACAUAUUCAUGUAUACGUAAUAUAUUCGUAUAUUUUAUAAACAUUUUUUAUAUUUUAUUAUAUAAAAUAUAAAUAUUUAAUUUUUUUUUAUGAGACGGAGUCUCGCUCUGUGACCCAGGCUGGAGUGCAGUGGUGCAAUCUCAGCUCACUGCAACCUCCACCUCCCAGGUUCAAGCAAUUCUCCUCAGUCUCCUGAGUAGCUGGGAUUACAGGCGCCUGCCACCACGCUUGGCUAAUUUAGUACUUUUAGUAGAGACAGGGUUUCACCACGUUGGCCAGGCUGAUUUCAAACUGACAUCAAGUGAUCUGCCCGCCUUGCCCUCCCAAAGUGCUGGGAUUACAGGCGUGGGAUUACCAUGCCUGGCCUUGUUCUGUUUCUUUUCCUAGGAGUCCCACAACGUGUGUGUUAGCACUGCCGAGAAUGUCUCACAGCUCUGGACGGUCUGCAUUUCUGGACCUGGUGCAGAUCCCAGGAUCCUGGACUCUGAUUUGAUGCCUUAACGGUGGAAGGGGGUUGAGUAUAUUUUUUAUGUGGGAGGGGUGUGGACUGUGGCCAGAGGAAAGACAGUGGCAAGGCAUUUCCAAAGGUGGCCACCAACAGUUCCUCCCACAAAGAGAAGGGGGCUUAUCUCUUCUUCCCUGCAAUAUUCUCCGGCCUUCUGACUUGCUCCGAACAACAGGAUGCAGCAUAAGUGAUAUUCUGGGACCUUCCAAGCCAGACUGAAGGGCCUUUGGUUUCUAUUUUCAUGCUCCUGGAACUCAGCAUCCAUGGAAAGAAGCUCUUGGCAUCACCCCAAGGAAGGGAGGCCCCGUGGAGUCGGGGAGGCCCAGCUAGCCUCUGGCCGCUGAAGCACCUAGCUGAGGUGCGGGACUGGUGAGGGCUGCCACUGGCUGUUCUGGUCUUGCUGAGCUUCCAGGCGAAUGCAGUCCCACCAGUGAUCCCGGGGACACCACGUGGAGCAGAACGACUUCCCAGCCAGGCCCCAGACAAUCUACAACACUGUGAAAGG